AGACGCCUCCGGUAGUGUAAAUGAGGACAAUGCCUGCUGGCCCACAUGACGGGGGGAUGUAGACGGCAGCGGCGCCAGUCGCUCCUGGCACCAUGGACGAUGCCACAGUCCUAAGGAAGAAGGGUUACAUCGUAGGCAUCAAUCUUGGCAAGGGUUCCUACGCAAAAGUCAAAUCUGCCUACUCUGAGCGCCUCAAGUUCAAUGUGGCUGUCAAGAUCAUCGACCGCAAGAAAACACCUACUGACUUUGUGGAGAGAUUCCUUCCUCGGGAGAUGGACAUCCUGGCAACUGUCAACCACGGCUCCAUCAUCAAGACUUACGAGAUCUUUGAGACCUCUGACGGACGGAUCUACAUCAUCAUGGAGCUUGGCGUCCAGGGCGACCUCCUCGAGUUCAUCAAGUGCCAGGGAGCCCUGCAUGAGGACGUGGCACGCAAGAUGUUCCGACAGCUCUCCUCCGCCGUCAAGUACUGCCACGACCUGGACAUCGUCCACCGGGACCUCAAGUGCGAGAACCUUCUCCUCGACAAGGACUUCAACAUCAAGCUGUCUGACUUUGGCUUCUCCAAGCGCUGCCUGCGGGACAGCAAUGGGCGCAUCAUCCUCAGCAAGACCUUCUGCGGGUCGGCAGCAUAUGCAGCCCCCGAGGUGCUGCAGAGCAUCCCCUACCAGCCCAAGGUGUAUGACAUCUGGAGCCUGGGCGUGAUCCUGUACAUCAUGGUCUGCGGCUCCAUGCCCUAUGACGACUCCGACAUCAGGAAGAUGCUGCGUAUCCAGAAGGAGCACCGUGUGGACUUCCCGCGCUCCAAGAACCUGACCUGCGAGUGCAAGGACCUCAUCUACCGCAUGCUGCAGCCCGACGUCAGCCAGCGGCUCCACAUCGAUGAGAUCCUCAGCCACUCGUGGCUGCAGCCCCCCAAGCCCAAAGCCACGUCUUCUGCCUCCUUCAAGAGGGAGGGGGAGGGCAAGUACCGCGCUGAGUGCAAACUGGACACCAAGACAGGCUUGAGGCCCGACCACCGGCCCGACCACAAGCUUGGAGCCAAAACCCAGCACCGGCUGCUGGUGGUGCCCGAGAACGAGAACAGGAUGGAGGACAGGCUGGCCGAGACCUCCAGGGCCAAAGACCAUCACAUCUCCGGAGCUGAGGUGGGGAAAGCAAGCACCUAGCAUGACAAUGGCCCCGUUGUGUGUGGUGGGGGUCGGGGUUGGGGGGCAUGGUGCAGUCGGCCUUCACGUAAACUAAGUAGGCAGGUAGGAUCUGAAGAAGGCACAGGUGCAAGUAAAAUUCGUCAAUUAAACCACUAUUUUGAUUA